ACAGCAUCCUGGCUGUGGCGCGUGCUGACUGAGCUAGUCUUGGGGUCCUGGAGAAGGGGGCUGGAGGCAUGCCCACAGCCUCCCCCCCAUGAGCUUGGGGCUGGCGGGGGCACAGGAGGUGGAGCUGACACUAGAGACGGUUAUCCAGACACUGGAGAGCAGCGUCCUGUGCCAGGAGAAAGGCUUGGGCGCGCGGGACCUGGCCCAGGACGCUCAGAUCACCAGCCUGCCUGCCCUUAUCAGGGAGAUUGUCACCCGCAACCUCUCCCAGCCUGAGAGCCCAGUCCUGCUGCCGGCCACAGAGAUGGCAUCGCUGCUGUCGCUGCAGGAGGAGAACCAGCUGCUGCAGCAGGAGCUGUCCCGCGUGGAGGACCUGCUGGCCCAGAGCCGUGCCGAGCGCGAUGAGCUCGCCAUUAAGUACAAUGCGGUCAGCGAGAGGCUGGAGCAGGCUCUGCGGCUGGAGCCUGGGGAGCUGGAGACGCAGGAGCCCAGGGGGCUGGUACGGCAGAGCGUGGAGUUGCGGAGGCAGCUGCAGGAGGAGCAGGCCUCCUACCGGCGCAAGCUGCAGGCCUACCAGGAGGGCCAGCAGCGGCAGGCCCAGCUUGUGCAGCGGCUGCAGGGCAAGAUUCUCCAGUACAAGAAGAGGUGCUCGGAGCUGGAGCAGCAGCUGCUGGAGAGAUCCGGAGAGCUGGAGCAGCAGCGGCUGAGGGACACAGAGCACAGCCAAGACCUGGAAAGCGCCCUCAUCCGGCUGGAGGAGGAGCAGCAGAGGAGUGCCAGCCUGGCCCAGGUGAAUGCCAUGCUCCGAGAACAGCUGGACCAGGCAGGCUCGGCCAACCAGGCUCUGAGUGAGGACAUACGAAAGGUGACCAAUGACUGGACACGCUGCCGCAAGGAGCUGGAGCACCGGGAGGCGGCGUGGAGGCGCGAGGAGGAGUCCUUCAACGCCUACUUCAGCAACGAGCACAGUCGCCUGCUCCUCCUCUGGAGGCAGGUGGUGGGGUUCCGGCGGCUGGUCAGCGAGGUGAAGAUGUUCACUGAGAGGGACCUGCUGCAGCUGGGAGGGGAGCUGGCCCGGACAUCACGAGCUGUCCAGGAGGCGGGCCUGGGACUGAGCACGGGCCUACGGCUGGCAGAGAGCCGGGCCGAGGCAGCCCUGGAGAAACAGGCCCUGCUGCAGGCCCAGCUGGAGGAGCAGCUGCAGGACAAGGUGCUCCGCGAGAAGGACCUGGCGCAGCAGCAGAUGCAAAGCGACCUGGACAAGGCUGACCUCAGUGCCAGAGUGACAGAGCUGGGCCUGGCAGUGAAGCGUCUUGAGAAGCAGAAUCUGGAGAAGGAUCAGGUCAACAAGGACCUCACUGAGAAGCUUGAGGCCCUGGAAUCCCUGCGGCUACAGGAGCAGGCGGCCCUGGAGACAGAGGAUGGAGAGGGGCUACAGCAGACCCUAAGGGACCUGGCACAGGCCGUCUUGUCAGACUCUGAGAGCGGCGUCCAGCUGAGCGGCUCUGAGCGCACCGCGGAUGCUUCCAACGGCAGCCUGCGGGGGCUCUCGGGCCAGCGGACCCCGUCCCCACCGCGGCGCUCCUCGCCCGGCCGAGGCCGUUCACCCCGCCGAGGCCCCUCCCCGGCCUGCUCAGACUCCUCCACGCUCGCCCUGAUCCACUCCGCCCUGCACAAGCGCCAGCUGCAGGUCCAGGACAUGCGUGGGCGCUAUGAGGCAAGCCAGGACCUACUGGGCACCCUGCGGAAGCAGCUUAGCGACAGCGAGAGCGAGCGGCGGGCCCUAGAGGAACAGCUGCAGCGCCUGCGGGACAAGACCGACGGCGCCAUGCAGGCCCACGAGGACGCCCAGCGCGAGGUGCAGCGGCUGCGGAGCGCCAACGAGCUCCUGAGCAGGGAGAAGAGCAACCUGGCCCACAGCCUGCAGGUGGCCCAGCAGCAGGCCGAGGAGCUGCGGCAGGAGCGGGAGAAGCUGCAGGCUGCCCAGGAGGAGCUGCGGCGCCAGCGGGACCGGCUGGAGGAAGAGCAGGAGGACGCAGUGCAGGAUGGCGCGCGGGUGCGCCGGGAGCUUGAGCGCAGCCAUAGACAACUAGAGCAGCUGGAAGGGAAGCGCUCAGUCCUGGCCAAGGAGCUGGUGGAGGUGAGGGAGGCGCUGAGCCGCGCCACACUGCAACGGGACAUGCUGCAGGCCGAGAAGGCCGAGGUGGCCGAGGCGCUGACCAAGGCUGAGGCUGGCCGCGUGGAGCUCGAGCUCUCCAUGACCAAGCUGAGGGCAGAGGAGGCCUCCCUGCAGGACUCCCUGUCCAAGCUGAGCGCCCUCAACGAGAGCCUUGCUCAGGACAAGUUGGAUCUGAACCGCCUUGUCGCCCAGCUGGAGGAAGAAAAGUCCGCCCUGCAGGGCCGGCAACGGCAGGCAGAGCAGGAGGCCACAGUGGCGCGGGAAGAGCAGGAACGGCUAGAGGAGCUGCGGUUGGAGCAGGAGGUGGCGCGGCAGGGCCUGGAGGGCUCCCUACGAGUGGCGGAGCAGGCCCAGGAGGCAUUGGAGCAGCAGCUCCCCACGCUGCGCCAUGAGCGCAGCCAGCUGCAGGAGCAGCUAGCGCAGCUCUCCCGGCAGCUGAGCGGGCGGGAGCAGGAGCUGGAGCAGGCCCGGCGGGAGGCCCAGCGGCAAGUGGAGGCGCUGGAGCGAGCGGCCCGUGAGAAGGAGGCGCUAGCCAAGGAGCACGCUGGCCUGGCUGUGCAGCUGGUGGCUGCGGAGCGUGAAGGCAGGACCCUGUCAGAGGAGGCCACACGCCUGCGCUUGGAGAAGGAAGCCCUGGAGGGCAGCCUGUUUGAGGUGCAACGGCAGCUGGCCCAGCUUGAGGCCCGCCGGGAGCAGCUGGAAGCCGAGGGGCAGGCCCUGCUGCUGGCCAAGGAGACCCUGACUGGGGAGUUGGCGGGCCUGCGGCAGCAAAUAAUAGCUACACAGGAGAAAGCCAGUCUAGACAAGGAGCUGAUGGCCCAGAAGCUGGUGCAGGCUGAGCGGGAGGCCCAGGCCUCUCUGCGGGAGCAGCGGGCAGCUCACGAGGAGGACUUACAGCGACUCCAGCGUGAAAAGGAGGCAGCAUGGCGGGAGCUGGAGGCCGAGCGGGCCCAGCUGCAGAGUCAGCUGCAGCGUGAGCAGGAGGAGCUGCUGGCCCGGCUGGAGGCUGAGAAGGAAGAGCUGAGUGAGGAGAUUGCUGCCCUGCAGCAGGAGCGCGACGAGGGCCUCCUCCUAGCAGAGAGUGAGAAGCAGCAGGCCUUGUCUCUGAAGGAGUCUGAGAAGACGGCGCUGUCAGAGAAGUUGAUGGGUACACGGCACAGCCUGGCCACCAUCUCCCUGGAGAUGGAGCGGCAGAAACGAGAUGCCCAGAGCCGGCAGGAGCAGGACCGGAGCACCGUGAACGCUCUGACGUCUGAGCUGCGGGACCUACGGGCCCAGCGGGAGGAGGCUGCUGCGGCCCACGCCCAGGAGGUGAGGAGGCUGCAAGAGCAGGCCCGAGACCUGGGCAAGCAGCGGGACUCCUGUCUUCGCGAGGCAGAAGAGCUUCGGACCCAGCUGCGUCUGCUGGAGGAUGCCCGUGACGGGCUGCGGCGGGAGCUGCUGGAGGCCCAGCGCAAGCUGCGUGAGAGCCAGGAGGGCCGGGAGGUGCAGCGCCAGGAGGCAGGCGAGCUGCGACGCAGCCUGGGCGAGGGUGCCAAGGAGCGCGAGGCCCUGCGGCGUUCCAAUGAGGAGCUUCGGUCUGCUGUGAAGAAGGCAGAGAGCGAGCGCAUCAGCCUGAAGCUUGCCAAUGAGGACAAGGAGCAGAAGCUGGCACUCCUAGAGGAGGCACGGACAGCUGUGGGCAAGGAGGCCGGGGAGCUGCGAACUGGGCUGCAGGAGGUGGAGCGCUCACGGCUGGAGGCUCGGCGGGAGCUGCAGGAGCUCCGGCGUCAGAUGAAGAUGCUGGACAGUGAGAACACCAGACUGGGCCGGGAGCUGGCGGAGCUGCAGGGCCGCCUGGCGCUGGGCGAGCGGGCAGAGAAGGAGAGCAGGCGGGAGACCCUGGGCCUCCGGCAGAGGCUGCUGAAGGGCGAGGCCAGCCUGGAGGUGAUGCGGCAGGAGCUCCAGGUAGCCCAGCGGAAGCUGCAGGAACAAGAAGGCGAGUUCCGGACCCGCGAGCGACGCCUGCUGGGCUCCCUGGAGGAGGCGCGUGGCACUGAAAAGCAGCAGCUGGACCACGCCCGCGGCCUGGAGCUGAAGCUGGAGGCGGCGCGGGCCGAGGCUGCAGAGCUGGGCCUGCGGCUGAGCGCAGCCGAGGGCCGGGCACAAGGCCUGGAGGCCGAGCUGGCCCGCGUGGAGGUGCAGCGGCGCGCGGCGGAGGCCCAGCUGGGUGGCCUGCGCUCGGCUCUGCGCCGGGGCCUCGGCCUCGGUCGCGCGCCCAGCCCAGCCCCGCGGCCAGUGCCCGGUUCCCCUGCCCGGGACGCACCCGCAGAAGGAAGCGGGGAAGGGCUCAACAGCCCCAGCACCUUAGAAUGCAGCCCUGGGUCCCAGCCACCAUCUCCAGGACCUGCCACCUCCCCAGCCUCUCCAGACCUGGACCCGGAGGCAGUGCGCGGGGCCCUCCGGGAAUUCCUGCAAGAGCUGCGGAGUGCCCAGAGAGAACGGGACGAACUUCGGACCCAGACCAGUGCCCUGAAUCGCCAGCUGGCCGAGAUGGAGGCUGAGAGGGACAGCGCAACCUCGAGGGCCAGGCAGCUGCAGAAGGCGGUGGCUGAGAGUGAGGAAGCCCGGCGCAGUGUGGAUGGGCGGCUGAGCGGGGUCCAGGCGGAGCUGGCGCUGCAGGAGGAGAGUGUGCGGCGCAGUGAGCGGGAGCGCCGGGCCACGCUGGACCAGGUGGCCACACUGGAGAGGAGCCUGCAGGCCACCGAGAGCGAGCUCCGGGCCAGCCAGGAGAAGAUCAGCAAGAUGAAGGCCAAUGAGACAAAGCUGGAGGGCGACAAGCGGCGCCUGAAGGAGGUUCUGGACGCCUCCGAGAGCCGCACUGUCAAGCUGGAGCUGCAGCGGCGCUCGCUUGAGGGGGAGCUGCAGCGCAGCCGCCUGGGCCUCAGUGACCGCGAGGCCCAAGCCCAGGCCCUCCAGGAUCGGGUGGAUUCCCUGCAGAGACAGGUGGCCGACAGCGAGGUGAAGGCAGGGACCCUGCAGCUGACCGUGGAGCGGCUGAAUGGGGCCCUGGCUAAGGUGGAGGAAAGCGAGGGGGCCCUGCGGGACAAGGUGCGGGGCCUGACAGAGGCCCUGGCCCAGAGCAGUGCCAGCCUCAACAGCACCCGGGACAAGAACCUGCAUCUGCAGAAGGCUCUGACCGCCUGUGAACAUGACCGCCAAGUACUCCAGGAACGGCUGGAUGCCGCCCGGCAGGCAUUAUCUGAGGCACGGAAGCAGAGCAGCUCCCUGGGCGAGCAGGUGCAGACGUUGCGAGGCGAGGUGGCUGACCUGGAACUGCAGCGGGUGGAGGCCGAGGGCCAGCUACAACAGCUACGGGAGGUGCUGCGGCAGCGGCAGGAGGGUGAGGCUGCAGCCCUGAACACCGUCCAGAAGCUGCAAGACGAGCGGCGGCUGCUGCAGGAGCGCCUGGGAAGCCUGCAGCGCGCCCUGGCUCAGCUGGAAGCUGAGAAGCGGGAGGUGGAGCGCUCAGCCCUGCGGCUGGAGAAGGACCGUGUAGCCCUCAGGAGGACGCUGGACAAGGUGGAGCGGGAGAAGCUUCGUAGCCAUGAGGACACAGUGCGGCUGAGCGCAGAGAAGGGCCGCCUGGACCGCACCCUCACGGGGGCUGAGCUGGAGCUGGCAGAGGCGCAGAGGCAGAUCCAGCAGCUGGAGGCGCAGGUGGUGGUGCUGGAGCAGAGCCACAGCCCGGCCCAGCUGGAGGUGGAUGCGCAGCAGCAGCAGCUGGAGCUGCAGCAGGAGGUGGAGCGGCUGCGCAGCGCCCAGGCGCAGACUGAGCGCACCCUGGAGGCUCGGGAGCGGGCCCACCGCCAGAGGGUGCGUGGGCUGGAGGAGCAGGUGUCCACACUGAAGGGCCAGCUGCAGCAGGAGCUUCGAAGGAGCUCAGCACCCUUCUCCCCACCCUCCGGCCCCCCAGAGAAAUGAGCUCCUGCUGGCAUCUGGAGAACACCCCUGUGCCUGGGACAGGGGAGGACCCUUCUUUUGGACAGCCCCCCCCCCCAGAGCCCGGUCCCUUGGGGGCCUCAAGCUGGGGUGGGAUGAGGAGGCGCUCUGCUGGCAGUGCUGAGGACGGGUACUCCAGCUCCAGGCCUGGAGAGGCUUCCCAGCAACACCUGCAGUCCAGCCCCCCUCUUCUAGGAUGAGCCACUGUAGAUCAUUAAAGUUCCUCCUUGAGAGGCUGAGCCGUAGCCAGGAUUGGGGAGAGCCCUUGUCUCUGGUCAGCCCUGGAGCAUGGGAUCGUGGGAAAGAGGAGGGGGACCAGGCCCAGGGCAGGGGUCAGAGGCCCAGGCCCUGACUUCGGCUUCCCAGAGAUCUCUCCGCCUUAGUUAAGAGCAUGUGUCGGGAAAUUCCUCAGAGUGCUCAGAGUCCCUGUAUUUUUAUACCUUUUUACAAUGUUAACUGUUCAGAACUGUUUUUUGUAACAAAACCUUGUUUUUAAAAAAGUUUGUACAGCUGUGUCCCUUUUCUAGACAAUUGGAGGAGACGUCGGGGGGAGACAGAUCCAAGCCCACCCUCGGGACAGUGACAGGCCUUCCAGGCAGCAUGGCAAACAAGUGCAGGUUUGGAUGUGAACGUGGGGUCUUGCCCUGGC